AGUGAAGAAUUUGGCGCCAUCUUGAGAAGGUCAAAGUGAUUCUUCGAUUAAAUGCCUUACUUAUCGCCUAGUGUGACCUGGCGCUUGGGUUUACUCUCCCCAGCAACUGCGCCUCAAACGCAAAGAAAACUGCAGGUCCUCGGGGAAGGAUCGAUUUCACCAUUCAAGAGAAAAAUCCAUUUCCCAGAUUCCUCCCCUUUAUGUAAACGUCUGGUACCUAGUAGACGUUAAAUACACGUGAGUUUUCCGGUUUUAUAAGAUCACAUACUGCAAACCAACAGUAAAUUACAUUAAUACGCAUUUCUUUAGAAAUUCUUAAUUGCUAGGCACUGACAUAUAAAUUGAGUUUGCUGUUGUUUUAGAGAGAAAAAUAGACAUAUUCAUUUUUUUUCAAUCAGGACAUGGUAUUCGUUUCCUUCUUAAGCUUCCCAUUUUUGAGGUAGGAAAGUAUUGGUGUGUGUCUCUAUCUCUACCUUGCUCCCUCAUUAGCAGGCUUAAUGGGCAGGAAUUAUGUCUGUUUUGCUUUCCGUUGGAUCCCCGGGUCUAGUAGAGCGCCUUGACACAUAGUAGGUACUCGACACAGAUGCUGGCUUCAUGAUGAAGCAAUUGUCCUCGAAUUAAUACAAAAGGGAAGAUUCAGACUCAGCGAGCCGGUACCAUUCGUCUAGGGACACACAGCCAGGAAGGAACCGAACCAGGAUUCUAACCCAGGAUUACCCAAGUUCGAAUUCUAAUUGAACAUAAGUCCUUAGCGACCUUGGACGGACUUACUAAACUGCCCUGAAUCUCGGCUUCCUUAGCUGCAAAAUAGGGUUAGGAAAAGUGGACUCGGUGCUCCUCUGCGCCGCAUUCCCGCAGCGGGAUUUGUGAAAGCGAACUUGAGCCCCACACUGCAGAAGCCCUGAGGUCCUGUCUCAACCAGAAUCCAGCACCCAGGACAAGCCCUCCAGCGACUUCAGACCUUCCCGCUCCCGACCCCGCCCGCCCCCGAGAGGCGUGGUCAAGGCGGGGCCAGAAGGCGGACGCGUGCACGGAGCGGUAAAGCGCAGGCGCAAAGCUUCGGUGACGUCAGAGAGGCGCGCUCCCAGCUCGGAGCCGACUCGCAGACGCGCCCCGCCCCUCGGCGUCGCUCUGGACUGGCGCAGGCGCAAGCCGGCAAGAUGGCGGCGGCUGGGGCUUUCCGUCUGAGGCGGGCGGCAUCGGCUCUGCUGCUGCGGAGCCCCCGCCUGCCCGCCCGGGAGCUGUCGGCCCCGGCCCGACUCUAUCACAAGAAGGUUGUUGAUCAUUAUGAAAAUCCUAGAAACGUGGGGUCCCUUGACAAGACAUCUAAAAAUGUUGGAACUGGACUGGUGGGGGCUCCAGCAUGUGGUGACGUAAUGAAAUUACAGAUUCAAGUGGAUGAAAAGGGGAAGAUUGUGGAUGCUAGGUUUAAAACAUUUGGCUGUGGUUCCGCAAUUGCCUCCAGCUCAUUAGCCACUGAAUGGGUGAAAGGAAAGACGGUGGAGGAAGCCUUGACUAUCAAAAACACAGAUAUCGCCAAGGAGCUCUGCCUUCCUCCCGUGAAACUGCACUGCUCCAAAUCUGUGCUGUUUCCAGCAGAGGAGAAAACUCAGCUUUCGCCAUAAUCCUGUUUCCUGUGUAUUUCUUCACUUCCUGUCUGGAUGGUAUUCCUGUCGGGGUCUGCAUCUGUAUAUAUGGAACAACUAAGCCCAGUUGUACAAUGUCCCCCUCCCUGCUAUCCUAAAAAAAAGCCCAGAUGCCUUAAGACUUGUACUUGGCUUUCCAGUUUGGUCUCUGUAUUAAAUCUAAUGCUUUUUCCAUCAUUUCUUAACCUUCUCAGGGAAAGAAGGAAUGAGAAACAUUAGCCUUAAUGCAUCGAUGGAGGUUUACUAACCAAAUUAGUUAAAAAUCAGCAGAGAGUCAGGCCUCUUGCCAAGGUAAUACUCACAGCAGAAGAGCCAGGUGCCGGGGCAGACACACUAACUCAUUCUUCAGGAAGCCUGGUCAGACCUAAGUUCUUUCCACUUGAUCUGGAAUUUUAAGUACCCAUAAAGAAAGGUCAUCACUUGUAAACAUUUUCACAUGGUUUCAGGAAAUCCCCAGCCCUUUUAUUAGGCCUUUUUAGGUACUGAAACCUUUAGCUGAUGUUCUCUGUUAUUUGCUUGCUUUCUGCUGUCAUUCCAGCUCUCUCAGUUUUUAUUUUCCCCAUAGCCUCACUUUGAAUAUUGACUCCUAAAUAAAAGUGGUCAAACUCUCGAUCACUAGAGGGUGAUGUGGCAAAUGCCAUCCCAUCAACAGAUUGACAUGAUCUUUUUUCCAAAGGGCAUGUCAACUUUUUUAUCAUGACAAGAUUUUGUCCAAAGCUAGACUUUGAUGGGAGCAGGCAAGAAGUAACAUUUCCUGUGUCCCUACUAUGUGUCAGACAUCUUCUGUAAGUCCCCACACUAUCCUGGCAAGAAAAGCAUGAUUAUCCCAGUUCUAUAGAAGAGAAAGUAGGGUCAAAGAGGCUAAGGAACUAGCCUGGGAUCACAGAUUUUUAACCCUAGUCUGUCUCCAGGAUCACCCGCAGGAGUAACUCAGCUCAGGAAGCAGCUGCUGACGUGCCCAGCAACUCCUCACCCCAGCUUUCUGGCUUGGUUACUCCAUUAGUCCCCACCAGCACCACUUCCUCCCAGCUCUUAAAGAUUCUAUUCCCAAGUCCAUUUCUUUCACAUCUAGAAACUUAGGCUUCUUUCCUUCCGUUACUUCCAGUGCUGGCUGAAGAUGCAAUCAAGGCCGCCCUGGCUGAUUACAAAUUGAAACAAGAACCCAAAAAAGGAGAGGCAGAGAAGAAAUGAGCCCUCCCUCGGCGAAGCCUCCAGCAGGCCACACCAGCUGUUUCCCACCUGCUGUGCAGUCACCUUAGAUGUUCAGAAGCCGCUUCCUCUCCACUGAAGAGCUAUGAGAUACGCACAAUACUUGCUGUUCACGUUAUGACUCUCAUGCAAGCAAAAUACACAGUUUCAUUGUUCUGAAUCCUGUGGUUUCUUUCAGCCCACUUUUAUCGCCUUAACCUAGUUAAUGUAUAUUUUGAAUUGUGUGUAUGACCUCAGAACUGAAAUUGAUAAUGAAGUUGCAAGUUUUGAUAGCCCGUGAAGUGCAUAAGUAUCUAAUUUUACCUGAAUUGAUUUGGGGGGAAAUUACCAGUAGAAUGCCUUGGUCUGAAUAUUUGAUAGAACCAAUUGUUGUACAUAAAACAGAUUGCGCAUAUAUAUAUAUGUAUAAAAAAUAAUAAAAUAAUGGAAGAUGAUGGUGUUCUCUAGUAA